GCAGUUCCCGGUCUCGCCUUCACUGCUGUGUGUCCUCAGCCUCUGUGGCCCUGUAACCUGCGGCAUUGGAAGAUCCACAGCUAACAUGCCAGGUGCCCCUGGCAGCCUAGAAAUGGGACCAUUGACAUUUAGAGAUGUGACCAUAGAAUUCUCUCUGGAGGAGUGGCAAUGCCUGGACACGGUUCAGCAGAAUUUAUAUAGGGAUGUGAUGUUAGAGAACUACAGAAACCUGGUCUUCCUGGGUAUGGCUGUCUUUAAGCCAGACUUGAUAACUUGUCUGAAGCAAGGGAAAGAGCCUUGGAAUAUGAAGAGACAUGAGAUGGUAACUAAACCCCCAGUUAUGCGUUCUCAUUUUACACAAGACCUUUGGCCAGAUCAGAGCACAAAAGAUUCUUUCCAAGAAGUAAUACUGAGAACAUAUGCAAGAUGUGGACAUAAGAAUUUACGAUUAAGAAAAGAUUGUAAAAGUGCCAAUGAGGGUAAGAUGCACAAAGAAGGUUAUAAUAAACUUAACCAAUGCAGGACAGCUACCCAGAGAAAAAUAUUUCAGUGUAACAAACAUAUGAAAGUCUUUCAUAAAUAUUCAAAUAGAAAUAAGGUUAGACACACUAAAAAGAAAACUUUCAAAUGUAUAAAAUGUAGCAAAUCAUUUUUCAUGCUUUCAUGCUUAAUUCGACAUAAGAGAAUUCAUAUUAGACAGAAUAUCUACAAAUGUGAAGAACGUGGCAAAGCCUUUAAAUCGUUCUCAACCCUUACUAAACAUAAGAUAAUUCAUACUGAAGACAAACCUUACAAAUAUAAGAAAUGUGGCAAUGCCUUUAAAUUUUCUUCAACGUUCACUAAACAUAAGAGAAUUCAUACUGGAGAGACACCUUUCAGAUGUGAAGAAUGUGGCAAAGCUUUUAACCAGUCCUCAAAUCUUACUGACCAUAAGAGAAUUCAUACUGGAGAGAAAACCUACAAAUGUGAAGAAUGUGGCAAAGCUUUUAAGGGGUCCUCAAAUUUUAAUGCACAUAAGGUAAUUCAUACUGCAGAGAAACCCUACAAAUGUGAAGAUUGUGGCAAAACUUUUAACCAUUUCUCAGCCCUUAGAAAACAUAAGAUAAUUCAUACUGGAAAGAAACCCUACAAGCGUGAAGAAUGUGGCAAAGCUUUUAGCCAGUCCUCAACCCUUAGAAAACAUGAGAUAAUUCAUACUGGAGAGAAACCCUACAAAUGUGAAGAAUGUGGUAAAGCUUUUAAGUGGUCUUCAAAACUUACUGUACAUAAGGUAGUUCAUACUGGAGAGAAACCCUACAAAUGUGAAGAAUGUGGCAAAGCUUUUAGCCAGUUCUCAACCCUUAAAAAACAUAAGAUAAUUCAUACUGGAAAGAAACCCUACAAAUGUGAAGAAUGUGGCAAAGCUUUUAACAGUUCCUCAACCCUUAUGAAACAUAAGAUAAUUCAUACUGGGGAGAAACCAUACAAAUGUGAAGAAUGUGGCAAAGCUUUUAGGCAAUCCUCACACCUUACUAGACAUAAAGCAAUUCAUACUGGAGAGAAACCCUACAAAUGUGAAGAAUGUGGCAAAGCUUUUAACCAUUUCUCAGACCUUAGAAGACAUAAGAUAAUUCAUACUGGAAAGAAACCCUACAAAUGUGAAGAAUGUGGGAAAGCUUUUAGCCAGUCCUCAACCCUUAGAAACCAUCAGAUAAUUCAUACUGGAGAGAAACCCUACAAAUGUGAAGAAUGUGGUAAAGCUUUUAAGUGGUCAUCAAAACUUACUGUACAUAAGGUAAUUCAUACUGGAGAGAAACCCUGCAAAUGUGAAGAAUGUGGCAAAGCUUUUAAGCAUUUCUCAGCCCUCAGAAAACAUAAGGUAAUUCAUACUAGGGAGAAAUUGUACAAAUGUGAAGAAUGUGGCAAAGCUUUUAACAAUUCCUCAAUCCUUGCUAAACAUAAGAUAAUUCAUACUGGGAAGAAACCGUACAAAUGUGAAGAAUGUGGCAAAGCUUUUAGGCAAUCCUCACACCUUACUAGACAUAAAGCAAUUCAUACUGGAGAGAAACCUUACAAAUGUGAAGAAUGUGGCAAAGCUUUUAGCCAUUUCUCAGCCCUUAGAAGACAUAAGAUAAUUCAUACUGGAAAGAAACCGUACAAAUGUGAAGAAUGUGGCAAAGCUUUUAGCCAUUUCUCAGCCCUUAGAAGACAUAAGAUAAUUCAUACUGGAGAGAAACCCUACAAAUGUGAAGAAUGUGGUAAAGCUUUUAAGUGGUCAUCAAAACUUACUGUACAUAAGGUAAUUCAUACUGCAGAGAAACCCUGCAAAUGUGAAGAAUGUGGCAAAUCUUUUAAGCAUUUCUCAGCCCUUAGAAAACAUAAGGUAAUUCAUACUAGGGAGAAAUUGUACAAAUGUGAAGAAUGUGUCAAAGCUUUUAACAGUUUCUCAGCCCUUAUGAAACAUAAGGUAAUUCAUACUGGAGAGAAACCCUACAAGUGUGAAGAAUGUGGUAAAGCUUUUAAGUGGUCCUCAAAGCUUACUGUACAUAAGGUAAUUCAUACUGGAGAGAAACCCUGCAAAUGUGAAGAAUGUGGCAAAGCUUUUAAGCAUUUCUCAGCCCUUAGAAAACAUAAGGUAAUUCAUACUGGAAAGAAACCCUACAAAUGUGAAGAAUGUGGCAAAGCUUUUAGCCAAUCCUCAUCCCUUAGAAAACAUGAGAUAAUUCAUAGUGGAGAGAAACCAUACAAAUGUGAAGAAUGUGGUAAAGCUUUUAAGUGGUUGUCAAAACUUACUGUACAUAAGGUAAUUCAUACUGCAGAGAAACCCUGUAAAUGUGAAGAAUGUGGCAAAGCUUUUAAGCAUUUCUCAGCCCUUAGAAAACAUAAGAUAAUUCAUACUGGAAAGAAACCCUACAAAUGUGAAGAAUGUGGCAAAGCUUUUAAUGAUUCCUCAACCCUUAUGAAGCAUAAGAUAAUUCAUACUGGGAAGAAACCAUACAAAUGUGCAGAAUGUGGCAAAGCUUUUAAGCAAUCCUCACAUCUUACUAGACAUAAAGCAAUUCAUACUGGGGAGAAACCCUACAAAUGCGAAGAAUGUGGCAAAGAUUUUAACAAUUCCUCAACCCUUAAGAAACAUAAGCUAAUUCAUACUAGGGAGAAAUUGUACAAAUGUGAAGAAUGUGUCAAAGCUUUUAACAAUUUCUCAGCCCUUAUGAAACAUAAGAUAAUUCAUACUGGGGAGAAACCCUACAAAUGUGAAGAAUGUGGUAAAGCUUUUAAGUGGUCCUCAAAACUUACUGAACAUAAGGUAAUUCAUACUGGAGAGAAACCCUGCAAAUGUGAAGAAUGUGACAAAGCUUUUAAGCAUUUCUCAGCCCUUAGAAAACAUAAGGUAAUUCAUACUGGAAAGAAACCCUACCAAUGUGACGAAUGUGGCAAAGCUUUUAACAAUUCCUCAACCCUUACGAAACAUAAGAUAAUUCAUACUGGGGAGAAACCCUACAAAUGUGAAGAAUGUGGCAAAGCCUUUAGUCAGUCCUCAAUCCUUACUAAACAUAAGAUAAUUCAUUCUGUAGAGAAACCCUACAAAUGUGAAGAAUGUGGCAAAGCCUUUAACCAGUCCUCACACCUUACUAGACACAAAACAAUUCAUACUGGAGAGAAACCCUACAAAUGUGAAGAAUGUGGCAAAGCUUUUAUUCAGUGCUCAUACCUUAUUAGACAUAAAACAAUUCAUACCAGAGAGAAACCUACAAAUGUGAAGAAAGUACCAAAGCUUUUAAGCAAUCCUCACACCUUACUAGACAAAACAAUUCAUACUGGAGAGAAACCCUACAAAUGUGAAGAAUGUGCCAAAGCUUUUUAA